AGGCGCAGGAGCGAGCGCGCCCAGAGUGGAGCUCAGCUGCUGGGAGCCAGCGGGGGAGCCUUGGGUUCCCGGUAAUGGAUCUGUGGGGCGUUUUCCCAGGGAAACUGGGUGGGAAGGGUAGCGGGAUCGCCGACUACAAGCGCAUUCUCCGCCUUGCCCGGGCCUGGGAAAGCUCUUCUGCUUCCUUUAGUCGUCCCUCUGGUUGACCCCACUUCUGCUCUGCGCCCCUCCUGGGGCCGUCUCUCACCGGGUGGCUUUGGCUGAGGGACGCUCUCUAUUCCUGAAGAGCUGUGCCUUGCCCGCCCGAGGAAAGCAUGUUAAUGGAGAGACUCGGAUCUCGCGGCCGCCACGGCCUUAUUGUCACCAUCCCAGCACCCCUAAACCACGACUUCAGCCUCCUCAACCCGCACCGUCAACGAUCUUGGAAGAUCUCUCCCCUUUCUGCCCGGGUAUUUUCACCCUGUUCGUGAAUCAGGCCUGGAAGGUGUGCCUGGGUUCCUUUAAAAUUAUUCUUUUGUUGGCUGCCUUUUCUAAACCCGGCCCUCCUUGUUCUCCGCCCCAAAAUCUUUGCCACGAAUGAGUACCAUGAAACCCUUGGGCACGCCCCUUCAGAAGCUGUUAUCCAAGACAAUCUAGUUUUCCUUUAUAAAUCACUUAAGACACUUAUGAAGUUUCUUGUUCUGAAAUUGCUGUACUGCAAUGAAGAAGAGGAGAAAGGUUACUUCAAAUCUUGAGAAGAUCCAUCUAGGCUAUCAUAAAGAUUCUUCAGAAGGAAAUGUUGCAGUGGAGUGUGACCAAGUGACCUAUACUCAUUCUGCAGGAAGACCAACUCCUGAAGCUCUUCACUGUUACCAGGAACUUCCUCCCUCUCCAGAUCAGAGAAAGCUUUUAAGUUCUUUGCAGUAUAAUAAGAAUUUGCUAAAAUAUUUAAAUGAUGAUAGGCAGAAGCAACCAUCUUUUUGUGAUUUACUUAUCAUAGUGGAAGGAAAAGAAUUUAGUGCACAUAAAGUAGUCGUUGCUGUCGGCAGUAGUUAUUUUCAUGCGUGUUUGAGCAAAAAUCCAAGCACUGAUGUUGUCACCCUGGAUCACGUAACACAUUCAGUUUUUCAGCAUUUGCUUGAAUUUCUUUACACAUCAGAAUUUUUUGUGUACAAAUAUGAAAUACCUCUUGUUUUAGAGGCUGCAAAAUUUUUGGACAUUAUAGAUGCAGUGAAGUUGUUAAAUAACGAAAAUGUUGCCCCUUUUCAUUCAGAGCUAACUGAAAAGUCAUCACCAGAAGAAACACUAAAUGAAUUAACUGGAAGACUAUCAAAUAAUCAUCAGUGCAAAUUCUGUAGUAGACAUUUUUGUUAUAAAAAGUCUUUAGAGAAUCAUUUGGCUAAAACCCAUAGGUCCCUUUUAUUAGGGAAAAAACAUGGGUUAAAAAUGCUGGAGAGAAGUUUCUCCGCAAGAAGAUCAAAAAGGAAUCGGAAGUGCCCUGUUAAGUUUGAUGACACCAGCGAUGAUGAACAGGAAAGUGGUGAUGGGUCAGACAAUUUGAAUCAAGAAAAUUUUGAUAAGGAAAAGUCAGAUAGAAAUGAUUCUGAGGACCCUGGAAGUGAAUAUAAUGCUGAAGAAGAUGAGCUAGAGGAGGAGAUGUCAGAUGAGUACUCUGACAUUGAAGAACAAAGUGAAAAGGAUCAUAAUGAUGCAGAAGAAGAACCUGAGGCUGGUGAUUCUGUAGGAAAUGUUCAUGAGGGGUUAACUCCAGUGGUCAUUCAGAACAGCAACAAAAAAAUAUUGCAGUGUCCUAAAUGUGAUAAAACAUUUGACCGAAUAGGAAAAUAUGAGAGCCACACCCGUGUUCACACAGGUGAGAAGCCCUUUGAGUGUGAUAUUUGUCACCAGCGCUAUUCAACAAAGUCUAACCUAACUGUUCACAGAAAGAAGCACAGUAAUGAAACAGAAUUUCAUAAGAAGGAGCACAAGUGCCCUUAUUGUAAUAAACUUCAUGCAAGCAAGAAGACUUUAGCCAAGCAUGUUAAGAGAUUUCAUCCUGAAAAUGCACAAGAAUUUAUUUCCAUUAAGAAGACUAAGAGUGAAAGUUGGAAAUGUGAUAUUUGUAAGAAAUCUUUUACUCGAAGACCACACUUGGAGGAACAUAUGAUUCUACAUUCUCAAGAUAAACCUUUUAAGUGUACCUAUUGUGAAGAACAUUUUAAAUCACGGUUUGCUCGGUUAAAGCAUCAAGAAAAGUUCCAUCUGGGUCCUUUUCCAUGUGAUAUAUGUGGUCGCCAGUUUAACGACACUGGAAAUUUGAAACGUCAUAUAGAAUGUACUCAUGGUGGAAAGAGAAAAUGGACUUGCUUUAUCUGUGGAAAAUCAGUACGAGAAAGAACUACUUUGAAAGAACAUUUGAGAAUCCACAGUGGAGAAAAGCCUCACCUUUGUAGUAUUUGUGGGCAAAGUUUUCGUCAUGGAAGUUCGUAUAGACUUCACUUACGAGUACAUCAUGAUGAUAAAAGAUAUGAGUGCGAUGAAUGUGGAAAAACAUUUAUCCGUCAUGAUCACCUUACAAAGCACAAAAAAAUACAUUCAGGUGAAAAAGCUCAUCAGUGUGAAGAAUGUGGAAAAUGUUUUGGUCGUAGGGAUCAUCUCACUGUUCAUUACAAAAGCGUACACCUUGGAGAGAAAGUGUGGCAAAAAUAUAAAGCAACAUUUCAUCAAUGUGAUGUUUGUAAGAAAAUUUUUAAAGGCAAAUCAAGUCUGGAAAUGCAUUUUCGAACGCAUUCAGGUGAAAAACCAUACAAGUGUCAAAUUUGCAAUCAGUCUUUUAGAAUUAAGAAAACAUUAACAAAACACCUGGUUAUUCAUUCUGAUGCCCGACCUUUCAACUGUCAGCACUGUAAUGCAACAUUUAAGCGGAAAGACAAGCUGAAAUACCACAUUGACCAUGUUCAUGAAAUAAAAUCUCCUGAUGAUCCUCUCAGUACUUCUGAGGAAAAACUUGUAUCCUUGCCAGUUGAGUACUCAUCUGAUGACAAAAUCUUUCAAACAGAAACAAAACAAUAUAUGGACCAGCCCAAAGUUUAUCAGUCGGAAGCCAAGACGAUGUUACAGAAUGUAUCUGCUGAAGUAUGUGUUCCAGUAACUCUGGUUCCAGUUCAGAUGCCUGACACUCCGAGUGACCUAGUGCGUCAUACUACCACACUCCCACCAUCUUCUCAUGAGAUUCUGUCACCACAGCCACAGUCAACUGAUUAUCCACGAGCAGCGGAUUUAGCUUUUCUGGAAAAAUAUACUCUUACUCCUCAACCUGCAAAUAUAGUUCACCCAGUUCGACCUGAACAAAUGCUAGAUCCUAGAGAACAAUCUUAUCUUGGAACAUUACUGGGCCUUGAUAGCACUACUGGUGUUCAAAAUAUUUCUACGAAUGAGCAUCAUUCAUGAGUAAAUCUAAACAUUCCACAGAUUUUUGGAUGGUUAUAUGCUAAUGGUAGAGAUGAUAGCUUUUAAAUUUGUGGGGCUGCUAUUUUCUUGUUUUCUCUAGUUUCUCAAGUCCUCAGAACAGUUUCAAAUCAAGAAAACUAUGUGUCUCUGUUUACUGAACAUGAAUAUUUGGACAAAAUUUCUGGCAUAAUAUUUGAAGUGCACAUUUUUGUGAUUUUUAAAGAUUAUUUAGUGCUAACUUUUAAUGGUUUCUUAAAUUUUUUGCAAUUAUUAGCUGCUGAUAUUAUGGAAGUAUUUUUUUUAAUCAUCAGUGGAAAUUUUUAUUCUUCUUUAGUCUCAUUCCUCUCCUUCUUCUUCCUAGCCCUUCUUACAAACAAGUUUGAGGACCAUGUAGCCUUUAAGAAGGAAUUAAGAGUACACUGAUAAUUGCAACUGUUUCUUAUCCUAAGAUUCAAUAUUACGUUAUACAAAUUUUUAAAAUUGAAAUUAGGAAUUUGAAUUUACAAGAAUGCCUUGGAUAUUUCUGUGUUGUCUUUCCAUUCAUACAUAAUUUUAGGUUAUCAUUAUCCUUUGGACUUUUGAUAUACUCAAAGCCAGAAAGCUUAACUAAUGUAAGAUUAGCUAUUAUUUGUAGGACUGAAAUAAUAAUCCAGAUAAUUGGUUUUUGCCUAUACUUCAAUUGUUAUGAAUAAGAAAGGCAAACAUAGGUCUGGGCAUUAAAUUAUACAAACUGAAAAUGUGUUACAAGAAAAAUAUGAGAGUUUUAACUAGAUGUUUUUCAAGGUAAGUUCACCUUUUGUACUUUACUAUUUAUUUCAGAAAUGUUGACAAUACAACAUAGCAUAUGUCUUCAUCUCACUAAGAAAAGAGCAGUUGUAACUCAAUGAAAUUUAAUUAAACAUGCUACUUUUGAUUUCAUUUACUUGGCUGAUAGAAACUCUGGGAAACAGAACCUAGAUAUUUUGUGUUCAAUUGUUAGAAAAGGUGCCAAACAGAUUAUGAAAUUUGUGCCUAAUUUAACUUAACAUUGUUUAAUUAAAUGGAACCACUACUUAUAUACAGAUUUACAUGCAAUCCAGAUCUUUAAUUUUGCCUUCACAAAAGCCUAAUGUCUGUAAUUAACCUUUAAUUUUUAUUUCUGUAUGAGACAAAAGUUGAGGACUUGGUGAAAGGAAAUAGCAGUUACAGCAAAACCUCAGUGAUUACAAUUGAGGAAAAAGUCAAAAUUAUAAAAUACCUUUAAAGACAUGCACUUUCCAUAUUUUCAAGUCAAUUUUAACUAAAAACUAAGAUAAUGUUUCCUAGUAGAGUUGCUUGAAGAUUAGACUAGACAGGGUUGAUUUAUUAUUAGCAUGUCAUUUGUACAUAAACUAGUAGAAAAUAGCAGUUUUAAAAGUUUUCUAUUUCAGUUUUGUUUACACUCCUAAUUGCUUUAAGCACUUUUUUUGUGUGUGUAAACUGUAAAGUCUAGCCCAGCCCUUGUGAAAAAAAAAAUCACAAAUAAAACAGUGAAGUUUUAAUGAAUAAAGUUUAAUCAAUUAGUAAUGGCGGAAACUGUCGCUGAAGCACUUAAGAAAUAAAGGUACUUUACAGCAACAUUCGCCAUACUAGCGGAGGUAAAACAAAAGAAAUAUUGAAAACUGAGGCAGUUAACCAAAGUAGCUCAUAUAAAUAAUAAAACCAAUCUGAGUUUAGCCUCAUUUGUCAAGGUUUGGUUGUAAUUGUCUUAAGACUAGUGGACAUACUUACUAUGUUCUCCUUUUUAAAGUAUUCUUAUUUCUUUGUGUGGAAAUGUUAUAUCUGGGGUACUUACAUGAUUGAGGUUGACUAUAUGAGGUACUGUUAGUCUGUUAGUCUUUCAAAUUGACUUUUAAAAAUACAUAUCUUUAUGAUUUUCAUCAUAAAGACUGGCAAUAUUAUAACUAAAAAUCUUACUAUAAUGAAAGAAAUCAUACAUAAAAAUGUAGCCUGCCUUACAUAUAAGCUAAUGUAGAAAAGUUUAGACUUAUAAAAAGGCAGAUAGUAUAUAUAUAUUUAUAUACAUGUAUGUAUAUGGUAUAUUAUACAUUUGGUGGCAGAAAAAGAAGAUACUGCAUUUUCACAUUGAAAAGAAUACUUUGAUUUUUGAAGGUAUUUACUUUAGGGUUCUUUUAAUAAUAAUGUCCGUCCUAAUGCUUUAAAUAUAUGAUUUAAUUGUAGGAAUUGGUUUACACAGAACUUUUUUGGAAUACAUCUCUUAGUAAAGUGAAAUAUAAUAAUAUAAUUGUAUUUAGUUACUAUUGUAGAUAACUUAAACUUGAGUAGUGAUUUACUGUUUUAUAAAAUGCUUUCAUAUAUGUUAUCUCAUUUGAACCUCAUAACCAGCCCUGAAAUAGUAAAAACAAGCUAUAUUCCCACUUUAUAAAGAAUUUGAGGUUAAGAUAAAAGGACUCAUUUAAGCUCACAUGGUCAGUAGGUGGCAGAGCUACUAGUAGGGAAAGAAGAAAGCUAGCAUUAAUGAAUGCUUACUAUGUGCCAGGUACUACAUCCUGUCAUUUAAUCUUAACCUAGUCUGGGAGAUGCGUAAUAUAAUUCUGGUGAAGUAAUAGUUUCAGUGGAUGAUUGAAAACAACAACAACAAAAACAAAAUGAAACUAAUCUGCUGCCUCUAAUUUCCAAAAAUGUAAGAAAUUUUACAAUUGUGAAAACCUCAUGGAUUUGGGCAAACUGAAUGUAUAUAGGCUUUUGACAAAAGUUGGCACAAAAAGUAUAAAAGGAGGCCUAUUCUUUUCAGUUGACCUUUUGUAAUAUUUGAUUUAGAGUAUUUUGGACAAAUGCUCUAUAACUCUAAUCCAUUUAUUUUGUAACUGUACUUAAAAUUUUGAAUCUUGCAACUAAGUUUAGCCUCAUUCAGAAUUUUUUUAUUUUGUGAGCAUAAUUUAUUGUUUUAAAUUAAUUUUUUAGCAGAUAGCAGUUAGCACUUAAUCUGUAAAUUGAAUAAUUUAUCAAGUGCAGGAAUGUGUUAAUCUAAUGGGUUUUGACUUAAAUGCACCAAAGAUUUUUAGUAGGUAUUAAAUAGUUUAAAAGACUUUAAAUUCUUUCUUGCUUGAAUAACUAUUUGUCCAAAGAAGCACAGUUGAAGUCCUAGAAUAAUGGAUUUUUUUAAAAAAAAAAAGUUGUUAGUUUGAAUACUGAGAUUGAUUAUUGUGUUUAUAUGUAUAAAAAUAGGAGCAAAAGAAAAUACUCUGGGAAUAGUCAUACUGACAAACCAAUUAUAAGUGAGAAUACUGUUUUCCUUAGUUUAAUUAAUACAAUGUUAUGUUUUUUAGAGAACACUACUAAAUGCUAAAUAAGCCUAUUUUUUACACUACACUAUCAAAAUAAUUUUUGCCUUCGAAUUUUUUUAAGUCAAGUUGAGGUUAUUUUUGUAAGAAACCCAACCUAUUUUUUUUGCAGCCUAAAAUCCCAUUUAAGGUUAGGGGUUGGUCCUUAUGCCAGCAAGAUUUAACCAACUGUAAAGAUAGUAGUCUUUGCAUACAUUUAAGUAAUUAAGGCAUUUAUUGCUGGGAGAAUAGGAGUAGCAAAAAUAUGGUUUUAAAUUGGUGCUUUAUUAGGUGACUUCCUUUUAGGCGAUGGCAGGUCAUGAAAUAGGUACACUAAUAAUUUUCUAUCAACCUUAAAAAGUGUCAAAGCAUCUUUGUAGGGUGACUCUAAACUGCUAAUUAAGGGUUAAUAAGUAAUUAUCAUUGGUUGCUUUUCAAUAUAAUUGCAAACAAAUUAAAAACACAGUUAAACUAAUAUGUUUAUAAGCUUGAGUUUUCUUCCUACCAUAUCACUCUCAUAUAUCAGUGAUGAAAUGUCAGAUUUUGAGCAGUAGCUCUUUGACAGUGUCCUUUUAUACCCAGUCUUUUCUGCAUUGAAUGCUUUGUGCCUUUUCGAUGUGUUGUAGUUGCUUAGAGUUGAUUCUGCUGGCUAGAUUGUACUGAUUAAUAGAUUUUUAUUUUUAUUUUUUUUUGGUUAUGGGUGUUAUGAUUGUGUUGCCUGCUGGUUGGGCAACUUUUUUUUUUUAGGUUGCUUUAUGUUUAUAUAGGCAAAUUGGCACUAAGUGUUAGUGUGAAUAUUUGUUUUUAUGAUUUAUAUAUCAUUUUAAAAAUCUCUGUUGUGGCCUUUAUAGUUACUGUGAAGCCACUCUUGGGCCUGUCUCUAUAUGCUUAUUAGAGGAAUCUGACAAGUAAAAUAAAAUGAGUAGUGUGUCUGCAUCUGUGUCUCUGUUUCUCUGUCUUUUAAAUAACCAGUAACCAUAACUACACAGCCCUGCACUGAAUGACCUUAUUUCAGUUUGCCUAAAACUGAACAAGAGGUGAUGGUUUGAGAUGAGUUUCUCAUUAGGAGCAGCAACAUCCCAACCAAUAUAUAAUGAGUUGAUCAACUCAGGAAAAAUUAGGACUUUAAAGAAGGUUGUAUUUGGAUAUUCUAAGAUUCAGUGCCAAAUUUAAAAUGCCUAGAAAUGUAUUCUACAAGUAGCAUUUCUAAAACUUUAAGUAGUGUUAUAGUAAAUGCUACUUGCUGUUAGAGUGAAUAAUGGAUAAUGUGAGAAUAAUUUUCUAAACGACUUCUAGAAACUAGACAGUUCUUCCUUAUAUCCUACCCUUUUCCACAUUUCUCUAAUGUGGGGUUUUUUGUUUGUUUGUUUGUUUUGAGGGUAGAGGGAAUCCCCUCCUUAUUUCCUCUAAAAUUGUUUUUACUUAAGAUACCUUUUCCCUAUAAUCUUAGCAUGCUUUCUGCUCUUUCUCUUUGGAAGUAGCAUUAAUAAGAUAGAUGUAAUAGGAUUAAGAUGUGUGGAAGAUGAGAAAAAGAAGGUUUUUGUAGAGAGAGUGCUUAUGUUUUGUUUACUCAUGUUUCAACUUGCUGUGUAUGAUCAUAAAUCUAUGAUCUUGAGAAAAAUCCUAAAACAAUUUAAAUUUAGCCUAUGCAGCCAAUUACAUAAAGAGAAAUUAAGGAUUAUAUUCAGAGGAGAAAUUAAGGAUUAUAUUUAGAGCACAGAGGUUAUACAAAGAAUAUAACCUUGUUUGGUCAAAUUCUUAGGUAAAGAAAAGUAAUCAAUGCUUGCAUUGCUGUUGGAGAUUCUAAAAGAUGUAUUGAAUGAAGAGGAUGUACACAUCUCAUUGUUACUGCGUAUUUUUUUGCUUGGUAUUCCUGCUUGCAUUAAAGCUGGACAAUGUACUGUGAUGUAAUUACAAAAUUUUUAUUCCUUCUAACGAUUGAACUCUUCUUAUCCCUAUUGAUAAAACUGUAUUACAAUUGAUGAGUGUGGCUGCCAGAAAAUAAUACAAAACUGGGCAUUUAGCUGUUCCACAUUGUGUAGUAAAUGUUUUGAUUAUGGGGAUUUACAGUGUAUAUUAAAGUAGAAAUGCUUUUGCACUUGUUUUCAGUCUCAAAUAAUAAUUUUUGUUUUUAAUUAAGGAUACUUUAAAAGCAAUGACAGAAAAAUCUAAAAUAUCAGAAUUAAUUAUUGUGAACUGUGUGUAAAAUAUCUUGUGAGUUUUAUACAUACUUUGGUUGUCUGAUGUUUCCUAAGUAUAAAUGUCUUUAUAGAAAAUUUCAGUUCUCUGUGAAGAGUAGGAAGUGUACUGUAUAUUGAACUAGUUCUUUGUGUUACUUUGAUAUUUAAAAUAAAUAUAAAGUUCUUUGGUCCUAA